ACUUCCGGGUUGGGCCGUGGGCUGGGGAGUCGUGGAGGCGCGGUCCUGGUCCCCACCCGGCGCGCUGGGACUCGCCCGCCUCCCGUCUGUCACCCCCUGCGCCUCGCCGGGACAACGGGGUGAGGGCAUGGGGGCGUGGGGCCCCAGCCUAUGUUCCCCGCGGCACUGGCGCGGCGGCCGCGCCGACCGAAGUCCGGGACGGGGGAGGGGCCCGAGCGCCAGCGGCCGGGCGGGAGUCUCAGGAGCGGGUUCCCGGUCCCUGCAGGCGGCCUGGCGGGUGGCAUCGAGAUCUGCAUCACCUUCCCCACCGAGUACGUGAAGACGCAGCUGCAGCUGGACGAGCGCUCGCACCCGCCGCGGUACCGGGGCAUCGGGGACUGCGUGCGGCAGACGGUUCGCAGCCAUGGCGUCCUGGGCCUGUACCGCGGCCUUAGCUCCCUGCUCUACGGUUCCAUCCCCAAGGCGGCCGUCAGGUUUGGAAUGUUCGAGUUCCUCAGCAACCACAUGCGGGAUGCCCAGGGACGGCUGGACAGCACGCGUGGGCUGCUGUGCGGCCUGGGCGCUGGCGUGGCCGAGGCCGUGGUGGUCGUGUGCCCCAUGGAGACCAUCAAGGUGAAGUUCAUCCACGACCAGACCUCCCCAAACCCCAAGUACAGAGGAUUCUUCCACGGGGUUAGGGAGAUUGUGCGGGAACAAGGGCUGAAGGGGACGUACCAGGGCCUCACAGCCACUGUCCUGAAGCAGGGCUCGAACCAGGCCAUCCGCUUCUUCGUCAUGACCUCCCUGCGCAACUGGUACCGAGGGGACAACCCCAACAAGCCCAUGAACCCUCUGAUCACUGGGGUCUUCGGAGCUAUUGCAGGCGCAGCCAGUGUCUUUGGAAACACUCCUCUGGAUGUGAUUAAGACCCGGAUGCAGGGCCUGGAGGCGCACAAAUACCGGAACACGUGGGACUGCGGCUUGCAGAUCCUGAAGAAGGAGGGGCUCAAGGCAUUCUACAAGGGCACUGUCCCCCGCCUGGGCCGGGUCUGCCUGGAUGUGGCCAUAGUGUUUGUCAUCUAUGAUGAAGUGGUGAAGCUGCUCAACAAAGUGUGGAAGACGGACUAAGCCUAGAGAGGCCGCAAGGGGACCGCCCCAGGCACCGCCAGAGUGUCCUGCUACCUUUGUCUCACGAUUCCAGUGCAGUAGUGCCAAAAGGCCCCUUCCCACGUCCCUCGAGCUCUGUAGCCUGGUCUGUGCAUUGUGGCUGUCAAAUCCAUGUGUCCCCCCUGUGGUCUGUGUGUGACACCACCACUGUGUCCCAGUGUCUGGCCCAGCCAUGGCUGGAUGUGCAUCUGGCCUAUGACCCUGUGCCUGUGUUUCAUGUUCUGUGUCACGUGACCCUGUGCCCCGCCUCCCGGGGUGCCCGUGUGGCCUGGGUCCUCGGCCCUGUAGCCCUGGCCCGGUCCCAGUCCGGUGCCUUCCACCCUGCCCUGGCCUACCACAGCUGCCUCCGGGCCUCGGCCUGGCUUCACCGCAUUCCAGGGGCUGCAGCCCCCUGCUUCUCCCGCCAUUGGCCUUAACUGGCCCUCGGGCCCUCUCUCCGCCCCGGACAGGGUGGCACCCACCACUCUCAGGACCACCCUGCCAAGGCAGAAUAAACCGGAUCCUGUUGCA